UGUAUUCUUAAUUUUUCCUCAAAUGCCUGAACGAUGGUUAGCUUUGCCUACUUUUCACCAAAAAGUAGCCUCUUUUUUCACUAAGGGAACUGACCCAAUGCUGUCUCUGCAGGAGGCUGAGCCCAUCCAAGUGAAUGAUGGCUCCCUGACCUGUCCGGGGUGUUCUCUUCUUGCUGUGCACCCACUCAGAUCGUUUGGGCUUACUCUGACAUAUUUCUAGAAAGGGCACUGUGGUGACCACCAGGUAAUGUGACAGCCCUGGCCUUGAAAGAGUGUCACAGCCACAGUGGAAGAGGACCCUGACACCCAGGACGCAGCCACCAGUAACAGGAUGUGAAUGGUUUGAUGCCAAAUGGAGUGGCACAGACAGGCCUUUCCAUCGAGGUUCACGAAAAGGGGAAUCGGCCUGUUCUGGAGAGGUUGGGAAAGCUCAUGGAGAAUUGGGGACAAGCAGGUUCUGAGGGUAUGGACAGGUGGGCAGGCUAUUUGAAGCUGGGUCCCUGUUCAGAUGUUAUCUCCCUGGAUAAGGGAGGAGGCACACUUAACUUUACUACUUACAGGCUGUGUGGCCUUGGAUGAGUCACCUAACCUCUCUAUGCAUUGGUUUGCCACCAGUAACAUGUUAAGCAGGCAGCAGUAACAUGAAGACUAUAAUAAUGUUAAUGAUGAUGAAAAUAGUUAUUAUUUAUGGAGAACAAAACCUGUAUCAGGAACUAUUCUCUACAAUUUACACAUACUAAUUCAUUUUGUCUCUAAAACAUUCCCAUAAAUGGUUACCAUUUUGAAGAAUGGUAACCAAAGUGUGGAGAGGUUAACAGAAGAAGUCAAGGCACAGAGAGAGAAAGUAACUUGUUCAUGGUUAUCUAGUUAGUGAGGAAGGGACCCCAAUUUUACAUCCAGGCUGUCUGGCUCUGAGAUCUUAACCACUCAAUCAUAGAGCCGCCUCAUGUUGUUGUUAGAGUCCGCUGGCAGUUCCGCUGGCAGAUGGUAACUGCCUAAUCCUUGUUGGCAUCAGGGAUCAUGGUGACUGGCCCUCAGGGGGGAUUCAGGUUUGUCUCUAGUGAGCUGGAUGUGGAGGGGUACAAAUGCCAGCCUCCGGGGUUUCCCAGCAUCCAGGAUAGGCAUGGGAUUCAGGUUUGAUGAUAGACACUGACAUUUAACUUUCAAGCCAAAAGGGGGAACCCCCCUAGUAAGGAAUUUAAUCAGUAAAGUCAUAAAUAGCAGUUAAAUAUUUUUGGCCCUGAUGUACAUCAUUCAGAGGUUUAUCAGAGCACUUAGGUGGGUUCAGUGUGGUAAUGACAGCCCCACAUCUCAAUGGCUCGCAGUUAGAAAGAGUGCCUUUCUUCUUUCUGCUGUCUUUGUCAGUAGUGGGCUGACUGUGACUCUGCUCCACACCCUCUUCUCUCUGAGCUUCAGGCUGAAGGGUCAGUUCCCUCUGGGAUAUGCUCUUCUUGUAUCAGAGGGAAAGAGCAGUGUGAGAACCCGGGGAUGGCUCUUUGGGUUUCCACUCAGAAGCGGCACAUGUGGCUUCUGCUCACAACCCACUGGCUGCUGCAGGUCCUGUGGCCAAGCCUAAUGUUAAUGAAGUGGGAAGUAUUAGCUUCCUAGAGUGAGGAUCCUAAAGGGAAGGGCAGGGAUUAUGUUAAGCGAAUAAUUCAUCUAUCACUGUAUAUUUUCUUACCCAUAGAUGUUCACUUCCCUCUCUCCUGCACACAAAAUGCCCUCCAAGAGAAAUAACCCAAGAGCUGCAUCCAGUCAGAGCAUCAUGAUCAAAGUCCUGGAUGGCGCGAUAGUCUGGAUGGAGAUCCUGUGGGUCUGGAUACCUAUAAACUAAAAGGACAAUUACCUGAAUCCAUAUAUCCAAUAUACAAUGAGCAAUGGGGACAGGAUGGCCAUGGUAGACACUCCUUUGCAGAAGAGGGAAGCAUGGGAAGAGUCAGUCCCGGGUCCAUAACAGUCGUGAAAUUCCACUGGACAGACACUGACCUGAUGACAUUUGAAGAUGUGGCUGUGGAAUUCAGCCAGUGGGAGUGGGGGCAGCUGAACCCUGCUCAGAAGGACCUCUACAGGGAGGUGAUGCUGGAGAACUUCAGGAACUUGGCCAUUCUGGGCCUUCUAGUAUCCAAACCAUAUGUGAUCUGCCAGUUGGAGGAAGGGGGUGAGCCCUUCAUGGUGGAGAGAGAAAUCUCAACAGGAGCCCACUCAGACUGGAAGAGAAGGUCUAAAUCCAAGGAAUCAAUGCCAAGUUGGGGAAUUUCCAAAGAAGAAUUAUUCCAGGUAGUAUCAGUGGAAAAACACAUUCAAGAUGUGCUGCAGUUCUCGAAGUUGAAAGCAGCCUGCGGUUGUGAUGGCCAGUUAGAGAUGCAGCAGAUAAAACAGGAGAGACACCUGAAACAAAUGUCAACCAUUCACAAAUCUGCCACCACCCUUAGCAGAGAUUAUAAAUGGAAUGGAUUUGGGAGAAGCUUAGGUUUAAGAUCAGUCCUUGUUAACCAACACAGCAUUCUCAUGGGAGAAGGAUCUUAUAAAUGUGAUACAGAAUUCAGGCAGACUUUAGGGGGAAACAACUCUCAGAGAACCCACCCAGAAAAGAAAUCUUGUAAAUGUAAUGAGUGUGGGAAGUCCUUUCACUUCCAGUCAGAACUUAGGCGCCAUCAGCGAUGUCACACUGGAGAAAAGCCGUAUGAAUGCAGUGACUGUGGAAGAGCCUUUGGUCAUAUUUCAUCCCUUAUUAAACAUCAAAGAACUCAUACUGGAGAAAAGCCCUAUGAAUGCAGUGAAUGUGGGAGAGCCUUCAGCCAGAGUUCGUCUCUUGUUCUGCACUAUAGAUUUCACACUGGAGAGAAACCCUACAAAUGUAAUGAAUGUGGACGAGCCUUUGGUCACACUUCAUCCCUUAUUAAGCAUCAGAGGACUCAUACUGGAGAAAAGCCCUAUGAAUGCCGGGAAUGUGGGAGAACCUUCAGCCAGAGCUCAUCACUCAUUGUGCAUUACAGAUUUCAUACUGGAGAGAAACCUUACAAAUGUAAUAAAUGUGGGAGAGCCUUCAGCCAGAGUUCAUCUCUCACUCAACAUUACAGAUUUCACACUGGAGAGAAACCCUACAAAUGUAAUGAGUGUGGAAGGGCCUUUGCUCAUACUGCAUCCCUUAUUAAACAUCAGAGAAGUCAUGCUGGAAAAAAAACCCUAUAAAUUCAGUGAAUAUAGAAGGGCUUUCAGCUGGAGUGCAGACAUCACUGGAACUUAAAGAAUUCAUAUCAGAGAGAGAUCCUAAAGGUGUAAUGUAUGUGGGAAGACCACAUCUUGUUCCACAUCAGGCAAUAAUUACUAAAGAGAAUCCCUGUCAAUGUCAAGAGGGGGUGGGCUUCCCCUCUCUUACCAAACAUGGGAGAAUCCAUACUAGUGAGAAACCACGUGAAUGUAAUGAAUGUGGGAACGCUUUGAUCAGAGGAUGCAUAUUAUUCAGCAUCAGACAGCCGACACUGGGGAGGAGCCUUAUCAAUGCAGUGAGUGUGGCAAGCCUUCAGUUACAUACUGAUUCUUUAAGAAAAUCAGAUAACUUGUACUGGAGAGAAAUCCUACAAGUGUGGUAAGUAUGGAAAAAUCUUCAGUUGUAUCUCUUCCUUUACUAAGCAUCAAGAACACAUACUAGAGAGAGGCCCUAUGAAAGCAGGAAAUAGAGGAAGGCCUUCAGUCAGGGCUCAUCCCUUAUUAAGCAUCAGAAAAUUCAUACCUGAGAAAAACCUGUGAAUGUGGGUAAUGUGGGAGAGCCUUCAGCCAAACCUCAUUGCUUUAUAAACCCCUUAGAACUCUCCCUACUAGCUGGAAACUCUGGUGACGUGAUGAAUGUGGGAAGGGCUUUGGUGGAUGUUCCACCAAAACACGUUAGAGAAUUUGUACAUUAGAGAAUUUGUGCUAGAGCAACUCUUCAAAUUUAGUGAAACUGGGAAAACCCAUUAGUAGAGUUCAAGCUUCAGUAUUCAUCUCAAAGAGAAACCUUGGGAACAUGAUGAAUGUGAGGAAAGUUCCUUUCCAACUUGAGAUGUAUAAAACUAGAGCUGAAAAGAAGCUGAGAAAUCACCUUGUCUGGUGAUUUUCUGCCUGGUGGGGCCAUUUGUAUAACGACACUUGUGCAUUGCCUCCUCAUGCUGUUACUGACGGGGCAGGGUGUCAUGCAUGGGUGCAGAGGAUGGAGGCUGAGAAAGGUAGACAGCUACCCAUGAUCUAGCCCAGUCGUAUUUUAGAGCUAAUAAAACUGAUGUUCAGAAAGUGACAUGCCUUGGCCUAUAGUCCUAACUGGGCUGGGCCUCUUUCCUGUGGUUCACAGCUGUAGUAUGGAGAUUAAUAGACUGGAUCUUUGCAGUACAACACCUCUAUGCACUUCUUUCUCUGUAGCACAUGUUACCUUUCUUUGUGAGGCAAUGGAGUGGUCUAGGAUUGAGCAAAAAGCAAUUUUUGUUACAUCUUUAUGCUAAUAGAUUUGGAAUUUUUGAAAUGAAAUGAAACCUUGUUUAAACAUUAAAAUUACUAAAAUAGGCUGGGCGCGGUGGCUCACGCCUGUAACCUCAGCACUUUGGGAGGCCGAGGCGGACAGAUCACGAGGUCAGGAGUUCGAGACCAUCCUGGCUAACACAGUGAAACCCUGUCUCUCCUAAAAAUACAAAAAAAUUAGCCAGGCAUGGUGGCGGGCGCCUGUAGUCCCAGCUACUUGGAAGGCUGAGACAGGAGAAUGGCGUGAAUCGGGGAGGCAGAGCUUGCAGUCAGCCGAGAUCACGCCACUGCACUCCAGCCUGGGAGACAGAGUGAGACUCCGUCUCAGAAAAAAAAAAAAAAAACAACUAAAAUAUGGGUAUUAUGCACAAUCCAGAUCUCAAAAACGUGAUUCUAAGUGAAAGAAGGCAGAUGCCAGAGACCAGGUAUUUUCUAGUACCAUUUUAGGAAAUGUCCAGAAAUGGCAGAUCUUCAGAAACAAAGUAACUGCAAAUGUUACAAGGAAUCUUUUUAGGGUGACGAAAAUGUUCUAAAACUAGAUGGUGGUGAUGGUUGAACGAUUUGGUAACUUCACUAAAAAUCAUUGAAUUGUUCACUUUAUAUGGGCAGAUUUUAUGGUAAAUAUACCUCAAUAAAAUCAUUUUUCAAAAUCAAAUUUACACAUAUACCAACCAUUGCUAAACAAGUAUUCCUGUUUUGUUUGUUACUUCAAGCCAUCUAUGCAUUUUUGGUAUCACUUUUUAUUUUCUGUAACAGUUACCCCUACAUUUACUGGGUCUCAGAACCUUGUCAGGCUCUGCUUUAAAGUUCCUACCAUGUUGGCUCUGUAACUCAGGUGGAGAAGCCUAGACCAGGAGCUGGCGUAGACCAAAGGAUACUUGCCUAAUAAGGAUUAGCUUAUACUGAGGAAAAUACUUUAAGCAUUUAAAGUCCAGAUGAGGAAGUUGAGCCCAGAAUUCAGGGAACCAGCUCAAAGUGGGCCCAUGCAGACAGGCUGGGUCUAAGAGUCCACAAGGUUGGCCAGGGCAGGUAGGAUGCACAGGAGGCAUCUGGAUCUGGAAGUACUUGGACAGCUGAGGUCAAGAUCACACAGAAAUUUAUUCCUGGACAGCCAAGGUUUACAGGAGCAGAAAUAGCAAAUAUUUUCUUGCUCCGUCUCUCCCUUUUUUCCCAGUGCCCUUUUCUGUACCUACCCAGAUCACUUUAUACCUAGACAUCUGUCACAAUUUUGUAACUGGUCUUCGUCCAAAAUCUGUCUCCUCUUCUCAUGUAUCCUUGCCAUAUUAACCAUACUUACCAGUUUGAACCCAGUGUCCUGCCCUCCAAAAAUCCUUUGCACGGCCUACAAGAUAAAUCCUCACCCCCCGUGUGUGGUAUAUAAUGCCCUCUUUAGGCUGCUCCAACCUCCUGCUGCUCCUGACAGAAGCCUCCAUUGCACACAAAUGCUCUCUUGUCAUCCCUCAGACAUGCCUUUCCACAUCUCAGCCUGCAAACCUUUACCUUAGCUGUUCUAUCAGCCGGGGGCACCUUCUCUACUUACCUAAAGCCUACAUAAUCAGUCAGAAACCUGUGUAAAUUUCCCUUCCUUGGAGAGGUGUUCUCUUGAAAACUGAUAUGAAGUCAUAUCUUACCAUUUGUAAUCAUAAACAUAUUUGUUUGUGUAAGUUUUUAAAAAUGGACAAUAUCUAGACUUGUGGUAAAUCGUAUCACUGUCUUGAUCUAUUUAAAUAAUUUUUUAUCACUUUACCACUUUCUUGUUUCCUGAACCAGAUGACAAUGGAAAAAGUCAAAUGGUAAAAUAUUUUAAGAGAUUUAUUCUGAGAUAAAUAUGAGUGACCUGUAGGCACAGUUGACCAGCAUUUGCCUUAAAACAGAGACCUUAAGACUAACAAAAACAGACUCUUUGUAGCAAUAACAACAUGACAGUAAGUCCUGAGAGAAAUCAAAGUGUUUUACGCCAAAAUAGAUUUAAGUCUGAUAAGAAACAAGUCUGACACAGCCCCAGGAGAUCCUGAGAACAUGUGCCCAAGGUGGCUCUUGUCAGGAGCAGCAGCAGGUUGGGGCAGCCUAAAGAGGACAUUACCAAACACGGGAGUGAGGAUUUAUCUUGUAGGAAGUGCAAAGGAUUUUUGGAGGGCAGGACACUGGGUUCAAACUGACGAGUAUGGUUAACAUGGCAAAGGUACGUGAGAGGAAGAGACAAUUGUGCUGUCAGGCUACAGCUUGGUUUCAUGCAUUUUUACAUUUUAGGGGAAUGUAAGACAUCAAUACAUGUAAGAUUUACAUUGGUUCGAUGGAGAAAGGCAGGACAACUUGAAGCUGGUGGGGAAGGGACAGGGACAGAGGGAGGGCCUUCUGGGUUAUAGGUGGAUUCAAAGAUUUUCUGAUUGGCAGUGGGUUUAUCCAAAGACCUGGAAUCAAUAGAAGGGAAUGUCUGGGUUAAGAUAAGGUGUUGUGGAGACCAAGGUUCUUACUGUGAGAUGAAGCCAGAAGGUAGCAGGCUUCAGAGAGAAUAGAUUGUAAAUGUUUCUUAUCAGACUUAAGAGAAAUUUAUUUUAGGAUAAAAUACUUAGAUUUCUCUCAGGGCCUGUUAUCUGUCAUGUUAUCUUAUUGCUACAAAGAGCCUGUUUUUGUCAGUCUUAAGGUCUCUGUUUUAAUGUUAAUGCUGGUCCACUGUGCCUGAAUUCCAAAGAGAGGAAGGUAUAAUGAGGUAUGUCUGACCACCCAUUCCCAUCAUGGCCUGAGCUAGUGUUUCAGGUUUACUUUAGAAUGCUCUUGGCCAAGUGGAAGGGUCGAUUCAGUUGGUUGUGUGCUUAGAAUUUUAUUUUUGACUUACAUAGACUAUCAGCUGCUUCAUGUCACAUCUCAUGCUUCUCUUAUGUUGCCCAGUUUUCUCAGUGCUUCCGACUGCAUGUUUUUGUACUAUAUGAAAAGCCUUCUUUCUAGAAGACUACCAAUUAAAUAUUUCUUUAGAAAAAUGUAA